ACCCACCCGCCGCACGUACUAAGGAAGGCGCACAGCCCGCCGCGCUCGCCUCUCCGCCCCGCGUCCAGCUCGCCCAGCUCGCCCAGCGUCCGCCGCGCCUCGGCCAAGGCUUCAACGGACCACACCAAAAUGCCAUCUCAAAUGGAACACGCCAUGGAAACCAUGAUGUUUACAUUUCACAAAUUCGCUGGGGAUAAAGGCUACUUAACAAAGGAGGACCUGAGAGUACUCAUGGAAAAGGAGUUCCCUGGAUUUUUGGAAAAUCAAAAAGACCCUCUGGCUGUGGACAAAAUAAUGAAGGACCUGGACCAGUGUAGAGAUGGCAAAGUGGGCUUCCAGAGCUUCUUUUCCCUAAUUGCGGGCCUCACCAUUGCAUGCAAUGACUAUUUUGUAGUACACAUGAAGCAGAAGGGAAAGAAGUAGGCAGAAAUGAGCAGUUCGCUCCUCCCUGAUAAGAGUUGUCCCAAAGGGUCGCUUAAGGAAUCUGCCCCACAGCUUCCCCCAUAGAAGGAUUUCAUGAGCAGAUCAGGACACUUAGCAAAUGUAAAAAUAAAAUCUAACUCUCAUUUGACAAGCAGAGAAAGAAAAGUUAAAUACCAGAUAAGCUUUUGAUUUUUGUAUUGUUUGCAUCCCCUUGCCCUCAAUAAAUAAAGUUCUUUUUUAGUUCCAAA